UUGGACAACAGAGUGAGAUUCUAUCUUUAAAAAAAAACAAAACAGGAUAUGCUUCUGGGCCUGACACCCAAGGCAUCCAGACGCUGGCCCUGGUGACCCCCUUACCUCCUCUCCCCCAUGCAGCCAGGGUCUUGGCAGGAAGCAGAAUUCAGCCCAGAUGAUUCCAAUAAAGAGACUUUAAUGGAGGAAUGACUUCUAGAGAGUAGGGUGAGGGGACCCAACAAGGAAGUGGGGGACGCAGAGGCCAGCAGCAGCAGCAGACACUCUAUGGCAGAGGCACUGGGGUGGCAAGGGAGCUGGGAAGCAAUGCCCCGUCUUCCUCCUCUUCCCUCUCUGCCAUCUUCUCUGAGUGCCUCCCAUUGGCUCAAUCCCACUGGAAGCCAGAAGGCCUGGGGAACUGGGACAACAGGGACCAAUACGUGUCAGAGAAGGACAGACGAUGGACCUGGUGGGUGUGUGGGGCAAAUGGAGGACCUCCUGUAUACCCCCAGCACCCCCAGGCUUGGGACUCUUGCUGGCAUCUGCACCUUUGUAGUGGCAGUGCCCUACUGGAUAAACCUGUCAGUCCUUCUCCACCUGGCAAACUCCUGCAUCUUCAGUCUCAUUUGGACAUUCCCGUUUCUGUACCUCCAUCGUGGUACUCAACACACAGCAAUCAAGACUGCCUGCCCACGACUCUGCCCCCUCCCUGGACCAAGCUCCUUCAAGGAGUGACCCCAUCUUUUAAUUGUUGAGAGCACGCAGUAAAUGGCAGGUGAGCAGGGCUAGGGUGACAUGAGUGAGGCAGUAGCCCUUGGUGUGAGAUUUAAGCGGGGGAGGAAGGGAGUUUGCUAGAAAUCUUAGUAAUCAAGACAAAAUAUUUGAAUACAAUAUUUAAAAAAAAAUCAAAUCAUCAAACUACAGCCCAUGGGUUGGCUACCUCUUUUGAGCGCCCACCCAAACUGGAAUAGCUCCCAAGACCUCUAGCAUGGUGUUCAAAAAUUAUUUUUGAGUUGGGCGCAGUGGCUUAUGCCUGUAAUCUCAGCACUUUGGGAGGCCGAGGCGGGCUGAUCACUAGGUCAGGAGAUUGAGAUCAUCCUGGCUAACGCGGUGAAACCCCGUCUGUACUAAAAUUACAAAAAAUUAGCUGAGCUUGGUGGCACGCACCUGUAGUCCCAGCUACUCGGGAGGCUGAGGCAGGAGAAUUUCUUGAACCCAGGAGGCGGAGGUUGCAGUGAGCAACCUCCACUCCAGCCUGGGCGACAGAGCGAGACUCUGUCUCAAAAAAAAAAAAAAAGGGUUCACAAUGCAGGACUCAUCUUUACUUAACAUACCCUCUAUUCACCCUGAUAUUUUCUAUUCUAGUCUAGUUUAUUUGGCGUCAUUAAAAAGUGCUGCUCAUACCUUUCUUUUCUUUUCUUUCUUUUUUCUUUUUUUUGAGAUAGAGUUUCACUCUUGUUGCCCAGGCUGGAGUGCAAUGGCAUGAUCUUGGCUCACCACAACCUCUGCCUCCUGGGUUCAAGCGAUUCUCCUGCCUCAGCCUCCCGAGUAGCUGGGAUUACAGACAUGUGACACCAUGCCUGGCUAAUUUUGUAUUUUUAGUAGAGACGGGGUUUCUCCAUGUUGGCCAGGCUGGCCUCAAACUCCCAACCUCAGGUGAUCCGCCCGCCUCAGCCUCCCAAAGUCCUGGGAUUAUAAGCGUGAGCCACCAUGCCCAGCCUGCCCAUAACCUUUCAAAUUCUGGCUUGAAAAACAUUGAGCCUGUCAUAUCAUCCUGCUUAAUUUUCUCUGCUUUUAGCUGCCUGAUACUUCCUUCUUAUGAUUUGUCUCUUUGCUGAUCUCCCGUCUUGCCUUCGGGGUACAGCUCCCUGAAAGCAGGAACCCCAUCUAGCUUGUCACUGCUGUCUUCUCAGCUCCGGGAACAGCGUCUGGCACGUAGGCGGCAGGUGUCCCGCAGUGAGCUGUUGAGCAAGCGAUUUGCCCUGGGGCCCCAGCCUGGCCCGGGUCACCCUGGCAUGAGGAGAUGGGCCUGUUGCUCCUGGUCCCGUUGCUCCUGCUGCCCGGCUCCUACGGACUGCCCUUCUACAACGGCUUCUACUACUCCAACAGCGCCAACGACCAGAACCUAGGCAACGGUCAUGGCAAAGACCUCCUUAAUGGAGUGAAGCUGGUGGUGGAGACACCCGAGGAGACCCUGUUCACCUACCAAGGGGCCAGUGUGAUCCUGCCCUGCCGCUACCGCUACGAGCCGGCCCUGGUCUCCCCGCGGCGUGUGCGUGUCAAAUGGUGGAAGCUGUCGGAGAACGGGGCCCCAGAGAAGGACGUGCUGGUGGCCAUCGGGCUGAGGCACCGCUCCUUUGGGGACUACCAAGGCCGCGUGCACCUGCGGCAGGACAAAGAGCAUGACGUCUCGCUGGAGAUCCAGGAUCUGCGGCUGGAGGACUAUGGGCGUUACCGCUGUGAGGUCAUUGACGGGCUGGAGGAUGAAAGCGGUCUGGUGGAGCUGGAGCUGCGGGGUGUGGUCUUUCCUUACCAGUCCCCCAACGGGCGCUACCAGUUCAACUUCCACGAGGGCCAGCAGGUCUGUGCAGAGCAGGCUGCGGUGGUGGCCUCCUUUGAGCAGCUCUUCCGGGCCUGGGAGGAGGGCCUGGACUGGUGCAACGCGGGCUGGCUGCAGGAUGCCACGGUGCAGUACCCCAUCAUGUUGCCCCGGCAGCCCUGCGGUGGCCCGGGCCUGGCACCUGGCGUGCGAAGCUACGGCCCCCGCCACCGCCGCCUGCACCGCUAUGAUGUAUUCUGCUUCGCUACUGCCCUCAAGGGGCGGGUGUACUACCUGGAGCACCCUGAGAAGCUGACGCUGACAGAGGCAAGGGAGGCCUGCCAGGAAGAUGAUGCCACGAUCGCCAAGGUGGGACAGCUCUUUGCCGCCUGGAAGUUCCAUGGCCUGGACCGCUGCGACGCUGGCUGGCUGGCAGAUGGUAGCGUCCGCUACCCUGUGGUUCACCCGCAUCCUAACUGUGGGCCCCCAGAGCCUGGGGUCCGAAGCUUUGGCUUCCCCGACCCGCAGAGCCGCUUGUACGGUGUUUACUGCUACCGCCAGCACUAGGACCUGGGGCCCUCCCCUGCCGCAUUCCCUCACUGGCUGUGUAUUUAUUGAGUGGUUCGUUUUCCCUUGUGGGUUGGAGCCAUUUUAACUGUUUUUAUACUUCUCAAUUUAAAUUUUCUUUAAACAUUUUUUUACUAUUUUUUGUAAAGCAAACAGAACCCAAUGCCUCCCUUUGCUCCUGGAUGCCCCACUCCAGGAAUCAUGCUUGCUCCCCUGGGCCAUUUGCGGUUUUGUGGGCUUCUGGAGGGUUCCCCGCCAUCCAGGCUGGUCUCCCUCCCUUAAGGAGGUUGGUGCCCAGAGUGGGCGGUGGCCUGUCUAGAAUGCCGCCGGGAGUCCGGGCAUGGUGGGCACAGUUCUCCCUGCCCCUCAGCCUGGGGGAAGAAGAGGGCCUCGGGGGCCUCCGGAGCUGGGCUUUGGGCCUCUCCUGCCCACCUCUACUUCUCUGUGAAGCCGCUGACCCCAGUCUGCCCACUGAGGGGCUAGGGCUGGAAGCCAGUUCUAGGCUUCCAGGCGAAAGCUGAGGGAAGGAAGAAACUCCCCUCCCCGUUCCCCUUCCCCUCUCGGUUCCAAAGAAUCUGUUUUGUUGUCAUUUGUUUCUCCUGUUUCCCUGUGUGGGGAGGGGCCCUCAGGUGUGUGUACUUUGGACAAUAAAUGGUGCUAUGACUGCCUUCCGCCA